AAAUCGCUUCAGUUCCCCGAGCUGGCGACUUCGUCUGUAAAAUGCGAGUCAUAGCCCUGUCUCCUAGAUGGGCCGUGUGGAGGCUCAGUGGCGGGAACGCCUGCGGGGCAGCCGGGGUCCUGGGCGGUUUGCUAGGGACGCCUCACUGGGGGUGACUAGCAUGCAGAUACCCAUGCUCUGACUUUCUGCCCCUCCACUGACAUGGCCCACCGGGGUGGGGAGAGGGACUUCCAGACUUCAGCUCGACGCAUGGGCACCUCGCUGCUCUUCCAGCUUUCAGUGCAUGAACGGGAGCUGGACCUGGUUUUUCUGGAUCAUAGCUAUGCCAAGCCUUGGAGUGCCCACCCAGAUGCCAGUAGUGCCCGCCCCACCCGCAUGCUCUUUGUCACUCCCCGGCGGCAGCACGAAAGUACCAUUGAAUCAGACGUCCCAAUAGAUGUGGAGACGGUCACAUCAACGCCUAUGCCACUCUAUGACAAUCAGAAGGCACGCAGCGUGAUGAAUGAGUGUGAACGGCAUGUCAUCUUUGCCAGGACUGAUGCAGAUGCCCCUCCUCCACCAGAGGACUGGGAGGAGCAUGUCAACAGGACUGGCUGGACAAUGGCCCAGAACAAGCUAUUCAACAAGAUCCUCAAAGCCCUGCAGUCUGACCGGCUUGCCCGCUUGGCCAACGAAGGGGCUUGUAAUGAGCCAGUGCUGCGCCGUGUUGCUGUGGACAAGUGUGCAAGGAGAGUGCGGCAGGCUCUGGCAAGUGUGAGCUGGGAUACCAAGCUGAUCCAGUGGCUGCACACCACCCUUGUGGAGACCUUGAGUCUGCCCAUGCUGGCAGCCUACCUGGAUGCUUUGCAGACGCUGAAGGGGAAGAUCCCAACCUUGAUUGACCGGAUGCUUGUGUCAUCCAACACAAAGACUGGGGCUGCAGGAGCUGAGGCCUUGUCUCUCCUACUGAAGAGGCCCUGGGACCCUGCUGUGGGUGUGCUUUCUCAUAACAAACCAAGCAAACUCCCUGGCUCUCCGCUGAUUCUCAUCGCCUCCUCUGGUCCCUCCAGCUCUGUGUUUCCCACUUCACGCCGCCACCGCUUCUGGCAAUCUCAGCUGUCCUGCUUGGGCAAGGUCAUCCCUGUAGCCACCCAUCUGCUGAACAAUGGCAGUGGGGUAGGAGUUCUACAGUGUCUCGAGCAUAUGAUUGGGGCAGUGAGAAGCAAAGUGCUGGAGAUUCACAGCCAUUUCCCACACAAACCCAUUAUCUUGAUUGGCUGGAACACAGGAGCUUUGGUGGCCUGUCAUGUGUCAGUAAUGGAGUAUGUCACUGCAGUUGUCUGCCUUGGGUUUCCUCUGCUUACUGUGGAUGGCCCCAGAGGGGAUGUAGAUGAUCCCCUCUUGGAUAUGAAGACUCCAGUCCUCUUUGUCAUUGGUCAGAAUUCCCUUCAAUGUCACCCUGAAGCCAUGGAGGACUUCCGGGAGAAGAUUCGAGCUGAGAACAGCUUGGUGGUGGUUGGGGGAGCUGAUGACAAUCUCAGAAUAAGCAAAGCAAAGAAGAAAUCAGAAGGGUUGACUCAGAGCAUGGUGGACAGAUGUAUUCAGGAUGAGAUUGUGGACUUUCUGACUGGAGUGCUCACUCGUGCUGAGGGUCACAUGGGCUCUGAACCUCGGGAUCAGGAUGCUGAGAAGAAGAAGAAGCCCCGCGAUGUGGCCCGCAGAGACUUGGCCUUUGAAGUCCCUGAGCGGGGCAGUCGACCUGCCUCCCCAGCUGCCAAGCUGCCCGCCUCACCCUCAGGCUCAGAGGAUCUCUCCAGUGUGUCCAGCAGCCCCACCUCCAGUCCCAAGACCAAAGUGACCACAGUGACCUCUGCCCAGAAGUCCAGUCAGAUUGGAAGUUCUCAGCUGCUGAAGAGACAUGUGCAGCGGACAGAAGCUGUGCUGACCCACAAACAAGCUCAAGUUCCCAUUUCAUCAGAACCACCAGAGGAAGGAGAGAAAGAGGAUCUUAGGGUUCAGCUGAAGCGACACCAUCCCUCGAGUCCCCUUCCUGGCAGUAAGACCUCCAAACGACCGAAGAUCAAGGUGUCCCUUAUCUCCCAAGGGGACACAGCUGGAGGGCCUUGUGCUCCUUCCCAAGGAAGUGCUCCAGAAGCUGCAGGUGGGAAGCCCAUCACCAUGACACUGGGGCAGGCUUCAGCAGGGGCCAAGGAGCUCACAGGACUUCUCACCACAGCCAAGUCCAGUUCUUCUGAAGGUGGAGUCUCAGCCAGCCCAGUCCCUUCAGUGGUCUCCAGCAGCACUGCACCCAGUGCCUUGCACACACUGCAGAGCCGCCUGGUGGCCACAUCUCCUGGCAGCUCCCUCCCAGGGGCCACAUCAGCCAGCAGCCUCCUCCAAGGCCUCAGCUUCAGCUUGCAGGAUAUCAGCAGCAAGACCUCUGGCCUUCCAGCAAAUCCCUCCCCAGGACCAGCCCCACAGGCCACCAGUGUGAAGUUGCCCACCCCCAUGCAGAGCCUGGGUGCCAUCACCACGGGCACCAGCACCAUUGUCCGUACCAUUCCUGUGGCCACCACUCUCUCCUCCUUGGGUGCCACUCCUGGUGGGAAGCCCACAGCCAUCCACCAGCUGCUGACCAAUGGGGGCCUCGCUAAGUUGGCAAGCAGCCUCCCUGGCCUGGCUCAGAUCUCUAACCAAGCAUCAGGCUUGAAGGUCCCCACCACCAUUACUCUGACACUUCGUGGCCAGCCGAGCAGGAUCACUACACUGAGCCCUAUGGGCUCAGGAGCAGCCCCAUCCGAGGAGUCCUCUUCCCAGGUGCUGCCCUCCAGCUCACAGCAACAUGGAUGAACUUGGAGGACAUGUUAAGUGAAGUAAGUCUGGACAGAAAAAUACUGCGUGUUCUCACCCACAGGUAGGAGCUAAAAAAGCUGAUCUUAUAGAAGUAGGGAGUGUAGGUGGGAUGAAUAACUUCUAGUGUUCUAUAACACUAUAGGCUGACUAUAAUUAACAAUUUAUUAUAGAUUUUCAAAUUCCUAGAAAACCAGAUUUUGAAUGUUCCCAGGAUAAAGAAAUGAGAAAUGUUUUGAGGUGCUGGAUAUGCCAAUUAUCCUGAUUUGAUCAUUACACAUUGUAUACACGCUUUGAAAUAUUGUACUCUGCCCCAUAAAUACAUACAAUUAUAUGCCAGUUAAAAAUAAUAAAAGCUGGCCGAGUGCAGUGGCUCAUGCCUGUAAUCUAAGCAAUUUGGGAGGCUGAGGUGGGAGUAUCUCUUGAGCCCAGGAAUUCAAGGCUGCAGGGCACCAUGAGUCACCACUGCACUCCAGCCUGUGCAAGAGCGUCUCUAAAAAUAAAAGUGAAAAAAGAAUAGACACACCACAGACUCAGAUAAAAUGUUUGUAAUAUGUAUUUGACCGAGGACACACAUAUAACCAGAAUACAUAAAAGAAUUACUACAAAUCAUGAUUUAAAUGUAAUAAAUAUUUGCAGGCUUAAAUAGAGACAUUCCACAAGAAGAUAUCCAAGUAGCCAAUGUGCACAUGAAAGAGUUUUCAGUAUCACUGGUCAUGAGUAAAAUGCAAUAUUAAACCAAUAAAAUACCACUUUACACUCACUAGAAUGGCUAAAAUUAACAACAAUACCGAGUGUUAGCAAGGAUAAGGAACACCUGGAACUCUUAGACAUUGCUGGUGGUAGUCUAUUAUAGUAAACCACUUUGAAGAACUGUUUGAGCAAUUCCUCUCCUACGUAUAUACAAAAGAGAAAUGAUAACUUACGUCCACAAAAGUAGUGACUUCUACAAGUACAUUCAUAGCAGCUUUAUUCAUAAUAGCCCAAAACUGAAAAUAGACUGAAUGUCCCUUAAUAGGAAAAUGGAUAUACACAUUGCAGUAUUUUCAUAUAGUGGAACACUAUUUGGUAAUGAAAAGAACCACUGACAUGCAAUGACCUGGAUGAAUCUCAAUAGCAUGCUGAAUGGCAGAAGCUGGACCCAAAAGACUACACGGUAUGAUUCCACUGAUAGGAAAUCCAAAUUUGAACAAAACUAGUCUGCGGUUAUAGAAGUCAGAUCAUGAUUGAGAGAGACUGUAACCAGAAAGGAGUACAGAGACUUUUUCCGUCGGGGGGAAAUGUUCUAUAUCUUGUUUUGGAUGGACAUUACAAGGAUGUAUACAAAUGUUGAGACUCAGUUGAGUGAGAAGGGGCCCACAUCUGGUAAUAGCCAAGUAGCUCCUACCAGACCAUUCCAUGCACAUGUAAUAACUAUAAAUAAAAAAAUAGAAAACUUCCCAUAAGCUGCUGGAGAGCCACAGAAUCAGACAGAUAAUGGGAAGGUGGGUGACACUUAGAUAGAGUAAAACAGUGAAUUUUGUUUGUAUGGCUUGUAGUCUGAGGGCAAACCAUAGUCUGUACCAUGCAGAGCAGCUAAAACUCAGAAAUGUGCUGCUGUAACCAUUCUGUCCAGCUUGCAGAACAAAAUAGCAGAGGUUGGGUUGACCAUUGCAGCUGGAAAGUGAGGGGAUACUCACAGGAAGAAGAGAGUGAGCCUCAGAUAUUCUGCACACUGUGUCCAAACCUUCCUGUAGCUCCUAAACUACACAUGUGUGUGUUAGACUUCCAGCAGUCCAGCUAAGGCUAAAAGAAUUGAACUGAAAUUUCAGCUGCCUUCAACUGCAGGCAAGCAAUAUGCAGUUUGAGUCUAGUAAACUUACCUGCCUAUUAGCAUGAAUAAUCAGUAUUUUUCAGCAACAUUAUAGAAUCCAACAUUUUUGGAACAUAUGAUAUGUCCAGAAUAUGAUCCCAAAUUAUUCAGUAAAGAGGCAAAUAUUACCCAUGCUCAAGAGAAAAGGCAAUCAAUUGAGACUGACCCAGAGAUGAUGCAGACAUUGGAAUUAGCAAGCAAGGAAUUUAAAGCAGCUCUUAAUAUUACGCUAUAGGAUGUAAAGGAAAGUGCUCAUAAUGAAGAAAGUGGUAAGAAGUACAGAAGAGAAGUCCAAACUAGAAAAAGCCAAAUGGAAAUUCUGUCACUGGAAAAUUAAAUACUUGAAAUAGAAAAUUCAGUGGAUGGGCUUAAUAGCAGAUUGGAAGUUACAAAAGAGUUAUUGAUUUUCUUCUUUUUUUUUUUUGAGACAGAGUCUUACUCUGUUCCCUAGGUUGGAGUGCAGUGGCACUAUCUCCACUCAUUGCAACCUCCACCUCCUGGGUUCAAGCGAUUCUCCUGCCUUAGCCUCUAGAGUAGCUGGGAUUACAGGCGUGUGCCACCAUGCCCGGCUAAUUUUUGUAUUUUUAGUGGAGACGGGGUUUCACCAGCCUUACCAUUUGGCCAAGCUGGUCUCAAACUCCUGGCCUCAAGUCAUCCGCCCGUCUUGGCCUCCCAAGUGCCGGGAUUAUAGAUGUGAGCCACCGCACCUGGCCGAGUUACUGACUUUUAAAACAAAAACAAGUUAUCUGGGGGAGAGAAAAAUAAAAUUGAAAAUAGUGAAUAACACCUUAGGGCAAUAUCAAAAGAUCUAAUGUACAAAUAAUUUUUAAAGUCCAAGGACAAGAGGAAAGAGGCCCCCCAAGGAAAAUAUUUAAAUGAAUAAUAGCUGAAGUAUUUUUAUAUUUGGUGAAAGACAAAAUUUGUAGGUUCAAGAAUCUCAGUUAACCUUGAGCCUCAGUGAUAGGAUAUGGAUGUUCACUGUACAAGUCUUGCCAUUUUUUUCUCUGUGUUUGAAAUUUUUUAUAAUGUUAAAAAACAAAAUCCUCAAAACAAAACAUUUAUAUUGAAAGAAACAUUUAGAAGUACUCAGACACAAGUCCAGAUGAAGUAGACAGAGAUAUAGAAAGUGAGGGUGGUUAAGUAUCUAUAAAGUUUGUUGUUACCUUAAAAGCCUCAAAGAAAAUAUAGUCUGUAGCCAUCUACAGCUAAAAUUCUAAAUAUCAAUAUGAGGAUGGGGUAAGGGAGCAAAAGAUAAAAAGCAGCAUGUUGAAGCACUCGUGGAAAUAUAUUGGUAAAUUUAAGAAGCUUAUAAUAGUAUAUGAAGAUAAGAAUGAAUGCUAAUAUACCAGUAACCACCUUAAGAACAAAGAUAUAAUCUAAACCUUUUUUUUUUUUUUUGAGAUGGAGUCUUGCUCUGUCGCCCAGGCUGGAGUACAGUGGCAUGAUCUUGGCUCACUGCAACCUCCGCCUUCUGGGUUCAAGCGAUUCUCCUGCCUCAGCCUCCUGAGUAGCAGGGAUUACAGGCAUGUGCCACCACGCCUGGCUAAUUUUUGUAUUUUUAGUAGAGAUGGGGUUUCACCAUGUUGGUCAGGCUGGUCUCGAGCUCCUUACCUUGUGAUCUGCCUGCUUCGGCCUCCCGGAGUGCUGGGAUUACAGGCGUGAGCCACCGUGCCCUGCCCCUUAGGUGAUUCUUAAAGCGGGGAAACUAAAGCACUAGGCUUUGGGGCUCUCUUCUCAGGCAUCCUCCUCAAUUCCCAGAGGAGGGACCUGAGACUCAAAACAGAGAGUCUGCAGGGCUGCACAGCCGCUGGUUGAAGGCUGGGAAAGAGCCAGAUGUUUUCUAGAAGGGCUCAUUCUGUCUCACUGUCCUGGCCUAACAGGAGGUGGCAGCACUGGUUCUGAGUUCUUGCUACUGCUUCUCUGGAUUGGCCUCACUCAGGGAGUGCAGUUAUCUCAUGGGCUGGAAUCCUGGUUACUGGAAUGCAGAGACAAAAGUCUUGUACCUCCUGUGGAGCCCACUGUAGGCAUAGGAAACCUAACAUUAUUUGGCUCUAUGAUGUCUCUGUUUUGCAGGGAUUCCACACAUGACACUUUUUAAAAUGCAAACUUUUAUAUUCAAAUAUAAUGUAUAUGCAUAAAAGUGCACCAAUAGAAACUAUACAGUAUAAUGAAUUUUCACAAACAACACACACCUGUUUAACCAACAUACAGGUAAGAAAUAGAACAUUACCACACUAUCCUUCUGCUCCAGGACAACCUCUUUCCUGACUUCUACCACCAUAGGUUGGUUUCGCCUAUUUUUAAACUUAAUAAAGGUGGAAUUAUGUA